AGCAUGGUUUACUGAAAAUUUUAAGCCCACUGUUGAGACCAACUGCUCAGAGAAAAGGAUUCCUUUCAAAAUAUUGUUGCUCAUUGAUAAUUCACCUGGUCACUUAAGAGCUCUGAUGAGAGGCCAGGCAUGGUGGCUUAUGUCUGUAAUCCCAGCACUUUGGGAGGCCGAGGCGAGUGGAUCACUUGAGGCCAGGAGUUUGAGACCAGCCUGGCCAACGUGGCAAAACCCCGUCUCUACUAAAAAUACAAAAAGUAGCUGGGCGUGGUGGGUCACACCUGUAGUCCCAGCUACUAGGGAGGCUGAGGCAGGAGAAUCACUUGAACCCAGGAGGCGAAGUUUGCAGUGAGCCAAGAUCGCGCCACUGCACUCCAGCCUGGUGACAGAGCGAGACUCCAUCUCAAAAAGAAAAAAAAGAGCUUUGAUGGAGAUGUAUAAGGAGAUUAAUGUUGUAUUCAUGCCUGCUAACACAAUAUCCAUUCUGCAUCUGUGAGAUCAAGGAGUAAUUUCAACAUUCAAGUCUUACUGUUUUAAGAAAUAUAUUUUGUGGCCAGGCACAGUGGCUCAUGCCUGUAAUCCCAGCCCUUUGGGAGGCCAAGGAGGAAGGAUUGUGUGAGCCCAGGAGUUUGAGACCAGCCUGGGCAACAUAAUAAGACCUCAUCUCUACAAAAAAAAAAAAAAAUUAGCUGGACAUGGUGGCGCUUGCCUGUAGACCCAGCUACUUGGGAGGCUGAGGUAGGAGAAUCAGCUUCAUGGUCCCAGGAGGUUGAGGCUGCUGUGAGCCACGAUCAAGCCACUGCCCUCCAGCUUGGGUGAGAGAGCAAGCCCCAUGUCAAAAAAUAAAAAAUAAAAAAAAGGAAAAAAAUAUAUUUUGUAAGGCUAUGGAUGCCAUAAAUAGUGAUUUAUCAGAUGGAUUUGGUCAAAGUAAAUUGAAAGCCUUCUGGAAAGGACUAACCAUUCUAGAUGCCAUUGAGAACAUUUGUGAUUCAUGAGAGGAGGUCAGAGUAGCAACAUUAACAGGAGUUUGGAAGAAGUUGAUUCCAACCUUCGUGGAUGACUUAAGUUCAAGACUUCAGCGGAGGAAUUAGCUGCAGGUAUGGUGGAAAUAGCAGGAGUACAAGAAUUAGAAGUAGAGCCUGACAGUGUGACUGAAUUGCUGCAGUUUUAUGAUUAAACCUUAAUGCAUGAGGAUUUGCUUCUUACGGAUAAGCAAAGUAAGUGGCUUCUUGAGAUGGCAUCCACUCCUGGUGAUGAUGCUGUGAACACUGUUGAAAUUGACAACAAAGGAUUUAGAAUAUUACAUAAACUUACUUAAUAAAGCAGCUACAGGGUUUGAGAAGAUUGACUCCAAUUUUGAAAGAACUUCUCUUGUGGAUAAAACACUGUCAAACAGCAUUGAAUGCUACAGAGAAAUCUUUCAUAAAAGGAAGUCAGUCGAGGCAGCAGAAUUCAUUGUUGUCUUGUUUUAAGAAAUUGCCGUAGCCACCCAAACCUUCAACAAACAGCCAUCAGCAUCAAGGCAAGACCCUCCACCAACAAAGAGAUUACAGUUCACUCAAGGCUCAAGCUGGAUAGAACUUAUACUGGCUUGCAGACUCUUGGAGCAGAGACGGUAGUGGAUGUUGAACUCCAUCGCCAUUCUCUCGGAGAAGACUGUAUCUAUCCUCAGUCCUCGGAGUCUGACAUCUCUGAUGCCCCUCCAUCUUUGCCUUUGACCAUUCCAGCCCCAGUGAAAGCUUCUUCACCAAUAAAGCAGUCACAUGAGCCAGUACCCGAUACCUCUGUGGAGAAAGGAUUCCCAGCUAGCACUGAAGCUGAACGACACACUCCGUUUUAUGCUUUGCCAUCUUCAUUGGAAAGAACACCCACCAAAAUGACUACAUCCCAGAAAGUUACCUUUUGUUCCCAUGGCAAUUCAGCUUUCCAGCCAAUAGCAUCAAGCUGCAAAAUUGUUCCACAAAGUCAGGUUCCUAAUCCUGAGUCACCUGGAAAAUCCUUCCAGCCCAUCACCAUGAGCUGCAAGAUUGUGUCAGGUUCCCCAAUAUCAACUCCAAGCCCAUCACCAUUGCCUCGAACCCCGACUUCCACUCCAGUCCACGUGAAGCAAGGCACUGCCGGCUCUGUUAUUAAUAAUCCUUAUGUUAUCAUGGACAAGCAGCCGGGGCAGGUGAUUGGAGCCACCACUCCCAGUACAGGAAGUCCUACAAACAAGAUCUCCACGGCUUCUCAGGUCUCCCAAGGAACAGGUUCCCCUGUUCCUAAAAUUCAUGGAAGUAGUUUUGUAACAUCUACUGUCAAGCAGGAGGAUUCUUUGUUUGCAUCUAUGCCACCUCUUUGCCCAAUUGGGAGUCACCCUAAGGUUCAAAGCCCCAAACCUAUAACAGGAGGACUUGGAGCUUUCACAAAAGUGAUCAUCAAACAGGAACCUGGUGAAGCCCCUCACGUGCCCGCAACAGGAGCUGCCAGCCAGUCACCACUCCCGCAGUAUGUGACUGUGAAAGGGGGUCACAUGAUAGCUGUGUCCCCUCAAAAACAGGUCAUAACUCCUGGAGAAGGGAUUGCCCAGUCAGCAAAGGUUCAGCCCUCCAAGGUUGUCGGGGUACCAGUUGGGUCUGCUUUACCUUCAACAGUGAAGCAGGCUGUGGCGAUCAGUGGUGGCCAGAUCCUGGUAGCCAAGGCCAGCUCUUCUGUCUCCAAAGCAGUUGGGCCAAAGCAAGUUGUAACCCAAGGAGUUGCCAAAGCAAUUGUGAGUGGAGGUGGAGGAACCAUUGUUGCUCAGCCAGUGCAGACCUUAACCAAGGCCCAGGUUACUGCCGCUGGUCCUCAGAAGAGUGGAUCCCAGGGUUCAGUAAUGGCAACGUUGCAGCUACCAGCCACUAAUUUGGCCAACUUGGCAAAUUUGCCUCCUGGCACUAAACUCUACCUAACUACAAACAGCAAGAACCCUUCAGGAAAAGGAAAACUGCUGCUGAUCCCUCAAGGAGCCAUCCUGCGAGCUACGAACAAUGCUAAUCUCCAGUCUGGCUCAGCUGCCAGUGGUGGGAGUGGUGCCGGAGGAGGAGGAGGAGGAGGAGGAGGAGGCGGCAGUGGCAGCGGUGGAGGCGGCAGCACAGGAGGAGGAGGAGGAACAGCAGGAGGAGGAACUCAAAGUACUGCUGGCCCUGGAGGGAUAUCUCAGCACCUGACUUACACAUCUUACAUCCUCAAGCAAACUCCCCAGGGCACAUUUUUAGUUGGCCAGCCAUCACCCCAGACUUCUGGAAAACAACUCACCACUGGGUCAGUGGUCCAAGGAACACUGGGAGUCAGCACAUCUUCUGCACAAGGACAACAAACGCUAAAAGUCAUCUCUGGACAGAAAACCACAUUGUUUACACAGGCAGCCCAUGGAGGACAGGCAUCUCUAAUGAAAAUAUCCGAUAGCACCUUGAAGACUGUGCCAGCCACCUCACAGCUCUCGAAGCCUGGAACCACAAUGCUGAGAGUAGCAGGAGGGGUUAUCACAACUGCCACUUCCCCUGCCGUGGCCCUCUCAGCAAACGGUCCUGCACAACAGUCUGAAGGAAUGGCUCCCGUGUCUUCAUCUACGGUCAGUUCUGUAACGAAAACUUCUGGGCAGCAGCAAGUGUGUGUGAGCCAGGCCACCGUGGGAACCUGCAAGGCUGCCACCCCCACCGUCGUCAGCGCCACGUCCCUCGUGCCUACACCAAACCCCAUCUCUGGGAAAGCCACAGUAUCCGGACUGUUAAAGAUUCACUCCAGUCAGUCCAGUCCGCAGCAGGCCGUCCUGACGAUUCCCAGCCAGCUCAAACCACUCAGCGUAAACACAUCUGGAGGGGUGCAGACGAUCCUGAUGCCUGUGAAUAAAGUGGUUCAGUCAUUUUCUACCAGCAAGCCACCUGCCAUUCUGCCUGUAGCUGCCCCAACUCCAGUUGUCCCCAGCUCUGCUCCAGCAGCUGUUGCAAAAGUGAAGACUGAACCAGAAACACCUGGACCGAGUUGCCUCUCUCAGGAGGGUCAGACAGCAGUGAAAACAGAAGAAAGUUCUGAGCUGGGAAACUAUGUCAUUAAGAUAGACCAUUUAGAAACUAUCCAGCAACUCCUAACUGCAGUAGUAAAGAAGAUUCCAUUAAUCACUGCAAAAAGUGAAGAUGCCAGCUGCUUUUCUGCAAAGUCUGUGGAGCAGUACUAUGGCUGGAACAUUGGAAAAAGGAGAGCCGCUGAGUGGCAAAGAGCAAUGACAAUGCGAAAAGUCUUACAAGAAAUCCUGGAGAAGAAUCCGAGAUUUCACCACCUGACUCCCCUCAAAACCAAGCACAUCGCUCACUGGUGCCGCUGUCAUGGCUACACCCCACCGGACCCUGAGAGCCUGAGGAAUGACGGGGACUCCAUCGAGGACGUGCUGACCCAGAUCGACAGCGAGCCCGAGUGCCCAUCAUCAUUCUCCUCUGCUGACAACCUCUGCCGCAAACUGGAGGACCUGCAACAGUUCCAGAAAAGGGAACCCGAGAAUGAGGAGGAGGUGGACAUCCUCAGCCUCUCCGAGCCAGUGAAGAUAAACAUCAAGAAGGAGCAGGAAGAGAAACAAGAGGAAGUCAAGUUCUACCUGCCACCAACCCCAGGGUCUGAAUUUAUUGGGGAUGUCACACAGAAGAUUGGGAUCACCCUGCAGCCCGUGGCACUCCACAGGAACGUGUAUGCGUCCGUGGUGGAGGACAUGAUCCUGAAGGCUACAGAACAGCUGGUGAAUGAUAUCCUGAGACAGGCUUUGGCAGUUGGAUACCAGACAGCUUCUCACAACAGGAUUCCCAAAGAAAUUACAGUGAGUAAUAUUCACCAGGCCAUUUGCAACAUUCCUUUUCUGGACUUCCUCACAAACAAACACAUGGGAAUAUUGAAUGAGGACCAGUGAGCGGAGUGAGGUGCCCUGGAGAAGCAGGCUUUGAAGGCACAGCGAAGCUGUAACUGAGGACCCUGCUGCUCGGGAAGGAGGUGGUUUCCAGUGUGACUCGGCAUGUCAUGGCUACCCAACCUUUGCCGCUGCCUGUUCCCACGUGUCACCAGCACGCUGCACUCCAGAUGAAAUCCUCCUAGGACAGGAGUUUGUUUCCUGAGUGUGGAGUGAGGCUGUCAGUGGAUCCGUGCUUUGUCGGCCAGCGUUUCUGCAGUCUUUGUAAAGGCCCCACGAGAGCGGGCCAGGCCGUGUGCCUCAGGCCCUUCUCCCUGGGUGUGCUUAAGGGGGCUCCUUGGGCCCGCCUCCCCAGGAGGUAGAAAAUGAGUGGCAGGCUAGAGAUUUCACCCAUUUUGUGGGCUGGAGUUACCAGUAGCUCCAGCAGUUACCCUGAAGAGAGAUUGGGCUUCAGCCUUCAGCAGGUGGUUCUCUCCCAUGCCUGGCCUUGGUGUGGAGGGGCUGUACUCUGAGCCCAAGUGAGUCAGCUAUAGGAAGAGGCCAUACCUAGAGCCAAGAACCAUGAAGGCCUGAGAGACGGCAGACUGAGCAGAAUUCCUUUUUUGAGCACGAGAGCAUUACUAGAACCAUUGUCAAAGCAGUGGCAAGGGACGGAGAGGUCCCAACAGGAGUCAGGAAGAGGUUUGAUUAUAACCAAGAAAACUCACUAUGCUAGGAAUAGACUGUGUGCACCAGUCCCAGACACUUGGCAGAAGUGUAGCAGCGUUACACAUGUGUGCGAAGCAGAUCGCAGGUUCCACGCCAUCUGCAUGGCCUGCAGGAGCUUCUGCUGCUGACCCCAUGCUGAGUGGCCAGUGGGGAGCGGCGCCCGGCAGGCUCUUCUGGGGUCGUCUGUCCUAUCCGUGGAUUGUAUAUACUCUUCUCUGUUAAGGAGUUUUUCCCAAGAAGAAAAGUAUUUAAAAGAAAUACCAGUGAGUGCCUUAAAGUUGGAGAAGUAACUGCCCAUGCCCAGAAAUAAGGAUGCCAGUGCCCAGAAGCAGUGAGAUUAGUCUGUGUCCACAAGCAGAGGCCCCCUCGAUGGGAGGGAGUGGCAGGCAGGAGAAGGUGGCGCUGCCAGGUGCCCGGGUCUAUUGGAGGCGCCCCAUCUCAGACUUCCUAACACAGCCUGUGUGGAAGGCAGAACAAAGAAUGCAUGCCCAGUCAGAAAUCUGUUCUAUUCUGCUCCAGGAAAAUCGGAAACCUGUGAGUCAGAGUCAGAGAAACUUACCCAAGCAACGUAAUUCCUGUUUUCAUGGGUCCUGUAGAUGUUUGAGUCAGGAAGGUAAGGCGGGGAGUGACUGAAUAAACUCUGCCUUUUAAAUUGAGCAUCUGGGCCGGGCAUGGUGGCUCACGCCUGUAAUCCCAGCACUCUGGGAGGUCGAGGUGGGUGGGUCACCUGAGGUUGGGAGUUCGAGACCAGCCCGACCAACAUGGUGAAACCCCGUCUCUACUAAAAAUACAGAAAAUUAGCUGGGCAUGGUGGUGUGUGCCUGUAAUUCCAGCUACUCGGGAGGCUGAGGCAGGAAGAAUCACUUGAACCCAGGAGGCGGAGGUUGCAGUGUGCCAAGAUCAUACCACUGCACUCCAGCCCUGGUGACAGAGGAGACCCCGUCUCAAAAAUUGAUUGAUCAAUUCAGCAUCUGAGGGCUGCAAGUACAGAAGGAAUCUAUUCUCAGCAGGGCAUAGGGCACGCACUGGCUUAACAGUUUAGUAUAUAAGGCUCAAAUAGUCUAUACCUGAACUGCUAUAAGCAAGGUCGAUAGGGAAGUGGAUAGAUUGCUUCAGCAAAGUGAACUGUGAGAUCUCCAGGACAGAGGGAGAAAGAUCUGAUCCAAAUGAGAACAGAUUGGUUAUUGCAGGUAUCACAGCCUAAAGAAAUUAUCUUUUUGCAAAAGAAAUAUUAAAUGAUUUAGCAGUCUCCACGUGUGUUAAUGUUUCAAACGUGUAUCAUAAUGUGUAUAAUUGUGUAACAAAAUUGUCUACAAUAAAUCUUUUGGUAUUUGUG